AGUCCUCCAUGGGGCUAGAAGAGAGAAGGACGGAGUCGAGUGGCACCCUAGAAGACGCUCUGUGCCUUCGGAGGUCUUUCUGCCUGCCUGUCCUCAUGCCUCUCCUCCUCUUGCUGCUCCUGCUGCCAAGCCCCUUACACCCCCACCCCAUCUGUGAGGUCUCCAAAGUGGCCAGCCACCUAGAAGUGAACUGUGACAAGAGGAAUCUGACAGCGCUGCCUCCAGACCUGCCGAAAGACACAACCAUCCUCCACCUGAGUGAGAACCUCCUGUACACCUUCUCCCUGGCAACCCUGAUGCCUUACACUCGCCUCACUCAGCUGAACCUAGAUAGGUGCGAGCUCACCAAGCUCCAGGUCGAUGGGACGCUGCCAGUGCUGGGGACCCUGGAUCUAUCCCACAAUCAGCUGCAAAGCCUGCCCUUGCUAGGGCAGACACUGCCUGCUCUCACCGUCCUGGACGUCUCCUUCAACCGGCUGACCUCGCUGCCUCUUGGUGCCCUGCGUGGUCUUGGCGAACUCCAAGAGCUCUACCUGAAAGGCAAUGAGCUGAAGACCCUGCCCCCAGGGCUCCUGACGCCCACACCCAAGCUGGAGAAGCUCAGUCUGGCUAACAACAACUUGACUGAGCUCCCCGCUGGGCUCCUGAAUGGGCUGGAGAAUCUCGACACCCUUCUCCUCCAAGAGAACUCGCUGUAUACAAUACCAAAGGGCUUUUUUGGGUCCCACCUCCUGCCUUUUGCUUUUCUCCACGGGAACCCCUGGUUAUGCAACUGUGAGAUCCUCUAUUUUCGUCGCUGGCUGCAGGACAAUGCUGAAAAUGUCUACGUAUGGAAGCAAGGUGUGGACGUCAAGGCCAUGACCUCUAACGUGGCCAGUGUGCAGUGUGACAAUUCAGACAAGUUUCCCGUCUACAAAUACCCAGGAAAGGGGUGCCCCACCCUUGGUGAUGAAGGUGACACAGACCUAUAUGAUUACUACCCAGAAGAGGACACUGAGGGCGAUAAGGUGCGUGCCACAAGGACUGUGGUCAAGUUCCCCACCAAAGCCCAUACAACCCCCUGGGGUCUAUUCUACUCAUGGUCCACUGCUUCUCUAGACAGCCAAAUGCCCUCCUCCUUGCAUCCAACACAAGAAUCCACUAAGGAGCAGACCACAUUCCCACCUAGAUGGACCCCAAAUUUCACACUUCACAUGGAAUCCAUCACAUUCUCCAAAACUCCAAAAUCCACUACUGAACCAACCCCAAGCCCGACCACCUCAGAGCCCGUCCCGGAGCCCGCCCCAAACAUGACCACCCUGGAGCCCACUCCAAGCCCGACCACCCCAGAGCCCACCUCAGAGCCCGCCCCCAGCCCGACCACCCCGGAGCCCACCUCAGAGCCCGCCCCCAGCCCGACCACCCCAGAGCCCACCUCAGAGCCCGCCCCCAGCCCGACCACCCCGGAGCCCACCCCAAUCCCGACCAUCGCCACAAGCCCGACCAUCCUGGUGUCUGCCACAAGCCUGAUCACUCCAAAAAGCACAUUUUUAACUACCACAAAACCCGUAUCACUCUUAGAAUCCACCAAAAAAACCAUCCCUGAACUUGAUCAGCCACCAAAGCUCCGUGGGGUGCUCCAAGGGCAUUUGGAGAGCUCCAGAAAUGACCCUUUUCUCCACCCCGACUUUUGCUGCCUCCUCCCCCUGGGCUUCUAUGUCUUGGGUCUCUUCUGGCUGCUCUUUGCCUCUGUGGUCCUCAUCCUGCUGCUGAGCUGGGUUGGGCAUGUGAAACCACAGGCCCUGGACUCUGGCCAAGGUGCUGCUCUGACCACAGCCACACAAACCACACACCUGGAGCUGCAGAGGGGACGGCAAGUGACAGUGCCCCGGGCCUGGCUGCUCUUCCUUCGAGGUUCGCUUCCCACUUUCCGCUCCAGCCUCUUCCUGUGGGUACGGCCUAAUGGCCGUGUGGGGCCUCUAGUGGCAGGAAGGAGGCCCUCAGCUCUGAGUCAGGGUCGUGGUCAGGACCUGCUGAGCACAGUGAGCAUUAGGUACUCUGGCCACAGCCUCUGAGGGUGGGAGGUUUGGGGACCUUGAGAGAAGAGCCUGUGGGCUCUCCUAUUGGAAUCUAGUUGGGGGUUGGAGGGGUAAGGAACACAGGGUGAUAGGGAGGGGUCUUAGUUCCUUUUUCUGUAUCAGAAGCCCUGUCUUCACAACACAGGCACACAAUUUCAGUCCCAGCCAAAGCAGAAGGGGUAAUGACAUGGACUUGGCGGGGGGACAAGACAAAGCUCCCGAUGCUGCAUGGGGCGCUGCCAGAUCUCACGGUGAACCAUUUUGGCAGAAUACAGCAUGGUUCCCACAUGCAUCUAUGCACAGAAGAAAAUCUGGAAAGUGAUUUAUCAGGAUGUGAGCACUCGUUGUGUCUGGAUGUUACAAAUAUGGGUGGUUUUAUUUUCUUUUUCCCUGUUUAGCAUUUUCUAGUUUUCCACUAUUAUUGUAUAUUAUCUGUAUAAUAAAAAAUAAUUUUAGG